GCCCAACAGCAUCUCGUGCCAGCUGAGCUGCGGUGUGUGGACCCGGGGAAUGGACCGGGCUGGACAACCUCUAAGACUUGGCUCCAGCUCAGCCUGUGAAGGAAUCACCUCUCUGAUCCCCACCUCUGCCCCGGAGUGCUAGACCCAGGGAGGAAGAGACCCCAUGGACCAGCCAGAGGCCCCCUGCUCCAGCACGGGGCCGCGCCUCGCGGUGGCCCGCGAGCUGCUCCUGGCUGCGCUGGAGGAACUGAGCCAAGAGCAGCUGAAGCGCUUCCGCCACAAGCUGCGCGACGUGGGCCCGGACGGACGCAGCAUCCCGUGGGGGCGGCUGGAGCGCGCGGACGCCGUGGACCUCGCGGAGCAGCUGGCCCAGUUCUACGGCCCGGAGCCUGCCCUGGAGGUGGCCCGCAAGACCCUCAAGAGGGCGGACGCGCGCGACGUGGCGGCGCAGCUCCAGGAGCGGCGGCUGCAGCGGCUCGGGCUCGGCUCCGGGACGCUGCUCUCCGUGUCCGAGUACAAGAAGAAGUACCGGGAGCACGUGCUGCAGCUGCACGCUCGGGUGAAGGAGAGGAACGCCCGCUCCGUGAAGAUCACCAAGCGCUUCACCAAGCUGCUCAUCGCGCCCGAGAGCGCCGCCCCGGAGGAGGCGAUGGGGCCCGCGGAAGAGCCUGAGCCGGGGCGCGCGCGGCGCUCGGACACGCACACUUUCAACCGCCUCUUCCGCCGCGACGAGGAGGGCCGGCGGCCGCUGACCGUGGUGCUGCAGGGCCCGGCGGGCAUCGGCAAGACCAUGGCGGCCAAAAAGAUCCUGUACGACUGGGCGGCGGGCAAGCUGUACCAGGGCCAGGUGGACUUCGCCUUCUUCAUGCCCUGCGGCGAGCUGCUGGAGAGGCCGGGCACGCGCAGCCUGGCUGACCUGAUCCUGGACCAGUGCCCCGACCGCGGCGCGCCGGUGCCGCAGAUGCUGGCCCAGCCGCAGCGGCUGCUCUUCAUCCUGGACGGCGCGGACGAGCUGCCGGCGCUGGGGGGCCCCGAGGCCGCGCCCUGCACAGACCCCUUCGAGGCGGCGAGCGGCGCGCGGGUGCUAGGCGGGCUGCUGAGCAAGGCGCUGCUGCCCACGGCCCUCCUGCUGGUGACCACGCGCGCCGCCGCCCCCGGGAGGCUGCAGGGCCGCCUGUGUUCCCCGCAGUGCGCCGAGGUGCGCGGCUUCUCCGACAAGGACAAGAAGAAGUAUUUCUACAAGUAUUUCCGGGAUGAGAGGAGGGCCGAGCGCGCCUACCGCUUCGUGAAGGAGAACGAGACGCUGUUCGCGCUGUGCUUCGUGCCCUUCGUGUGCUGGAUCGUGUGCACCGUGCUGCGCCAGCAGCUGGAGCUCGGUCGGGACCUGUCGCGCACGUCCAAGACCACCACGUCAGUGUACCUGCUUUUCAUCACCAGCGUUCUGAGCUCGGCUCCGGUAGCCGACGGGCCCCGGUUGCAGGGCGACCUGCGCAAUCUGUGCCGCCUGGCCCGCGAGGGCGUCCUCGGACGCAGGGCGCAGUUUGCCGAGAAGGAACUGGAGCAACUGGAGCUUCGUGGCUCCAAAGUGCAGACGCUGUUUCUCAGCAAAAAGGAGCUGCCGGGCGUGCUGGAGACAGAGGUCACCUACCAGUUCAUCGACCAGAGCUUCCAGGAGUUCCUCGCGGCACUGUCCUACCUGCUGGAGGACGGCGGGGUGCCCAGGACCGCGGCUGGCGGCGUUGGGACACUCCUGCGUGGGGACGCCCAGCCGCACAGCCACUUGGUGCUCACCACGCGCUUCCUCUUCGGACUGCUGAGCGCGGAGCGGAUGCGCGACAUCGAGCGCCACUUCGGCUGCAUGGUUUCAGAGCGUGUGAAGCAGGAGGCCCUGCGGUGGGUGCAGGGACAGGGACAGGGCUGCCCCGGAGUGGCACCAGAGGUGACCGAGGGGGCCAAAGGGCUCGAGGACACCGAAGAGCCAGAGGAGGAGGAGGAGGGAGAGGAGCCCAACUACCCACUGGAGUUGCUGUACUGCCUGUACGAGACGCAGGAGGACGCGUUUGUGCGCCAAGCCCUGUGCCGGUUCCCGGAGCUGGCGCUGCAGCGAGUGCGCUUCUGCCGCAUGGACGUGGCUGUUCUGAGCUACUGCGUGAGGUGCUGCCCUGCUGGACAGGCACUGCGGCUGAUCAGCUGCAGAUUGGUUGCUGCGCAGGAGAAGAAGAAGAAGAGCCUGGGGAAGCGGCUCCAGGCCAGCCUGGGUGGCGGCAGUUCUCAAGGCACCACAAAACAACUGCCAGCCUCCCUUCUUCAUCCACUCUUUCAGGCAAUGACUGACCCACUGUGCCAUCUGAGCAGCCUCACGCUGUCCCACUGCAAACUCCCUGACGCGGUCUGCCGAGACCUUUCUGAGGCCCUGAGGGCAGCCCCCGCACUGACGGAGCUGGGCCUCCUCCACAACAGGCUCAGUGAGGCGGGACUGCGUAUGCUGAGUGAGGGCCUAGCCUGGCCGCAGUGCAGGGUGCAGACGGUCAGGGUACAGCUGCCUGACCCCCAGCGAGGGCUCCAGUACCUGGUGGGUAUGCUUCGGCAGAGCCCUGCCCUGACCACCCUGGAUCUCAGCGGCUGCCAACUGCCCGCCCCCAUGGUGACCUACCUGUGUGCAGUCCUGCAGCACCAGGGAUGCGGCCUGCAGACCCUCAGUCUGGCCUCUGUGGAGCUGAGCGAGCAGUCACUACAGGAGCUUCAGGCUGUGAAGAGAGCAAAGCCGGAUCUGGUCAUCACACACCCAGCGCUGGACGGCCACCCACAACCUCCCAAGGAACUCAUCUCGACCUUCUGAGGCUCUGGUGGCCAGAGCAGGGUGGAAGACCCUAGUCAAAGUCCCUGUGGAGAGAACGGCCCAUUCCAAGGGCAGGAGGAUAUU